GCCGCCAUUUUGGAGCGAUCGGAGUGCCGCCCGCGGCCCCGAGUCGGUCUCGAGCCGCCGGCCGGCCGUGCCGGUGUCCGUAGGCGCUGCGCCCUCGGCCGGGCCCAUGUGUGUGCGGCCCGCCCGAGGCCGCCCGGGCUUUGCCUCCACCAGCGCCCUGGCCUCCGCUCGGGCCUCCACACGGGCCUCCGAAGAGCUGCCGCGACGCCCGGCCCGCAGGGCAGGUAAAGAGAUUAUAAAUCUUCCACUGAAUGAAAAAAAUUUUCUUAAAGCUGCAUAUACUCCAAGAAAAAAACCACAAAUGUUUUUCUGUUUUGCCUGAAUACAUGAUUUAAACAAGAGAUUUCCACAGAAGGGCGCUUUCAUGGAACUAUAUGAUCAUAUGGGCAACAUUCUGUUGCAGUCUACCUUCUGUCUGACGGAUAUGCCAUCCUGAAAAAGGAAAGAAGCUGAACUUCAAGUUCCUUUCAUUUAGCCUUGGGCUUCCACCUUCUCUGUGGCUAGAAACAGGACCGUCCAGAAGUCACCUGUAACUGCCCUAUCUUGCAAGUUCUGAUUUUGGCAAAAAAAAAAAAAAAAAGCCUUGACAAGGUUGGAUUCACUUCUUUCCCUGGAUUGUGUGUCAUCCAAGUACGUGAGACAUCUGGUAGUGCAUUUCAGAGAGAGGAGUAUCUGAUAUGUGUGUGGAGGCAGCCAUCUUUUCCUGAAAGUCCUUUUAGGAAUCAUUAUUUCUGGUCCUCUGAAGUUUGCCGCUACCACUCAUAAAUAUCUAUCCACACCCCUUACAAGAAGAAUAAGGAAGAUCUUAAGACCUAGAAGGAAAACUGAUUGCAGACCAGGCUUGGUGGCUCAGUGCCUGUAAUCCCAGCACUUUGGGAGGCCAAGGAGGGCAGAUUGCUUGAGCUCAGCAGUUCGAGGCCAACCUGGGCAACAUAGUGAAUCCCUGUCUCUACAGAAAAAAAAAAAAAAAAAACCCACCCCAAAAUCAAAACUGAAGGUAGUGUCAGUGUAUAUAUGGAGUCCCUUGUGCUGAAAGUCAAAGCAGCUUCAUUUUGGGGCCUCAAGAGCUCCAGCUCUGGGCUCUUCACCUCUAAGCCCAUGGGCAGUGCCCGCCCAGUGGUGUGUAUAGAUCGGAGGCUGCAGGGCCUCACCCUUAGCUGCAGCUGUCGCGUGCUGGGGAGCCUGUGCAGGAGGGUACAAGUAGGAAAGUGCCAUCUGCAUGGGAAGAAAAAUGCAGCAUCCUUGUAGUGCGGAUGGGGUCCAGGAGACCCAGGAGCUGCCCAGAGGACCUGGUGGCAUGCUGUAGAAAGCAGCCAGGUAGGUAUCUGGGGCCAGGAGAGGUUUUGGAGCUGAGAUGAGAUGUGUAGACAUCAAGUGAGUUUGAAUUAGCCAAAGCCAGAGGCUGUGGGAGUGUGGCUGGACGAUGGAGGCUCCCGUGUCAGGGGUCCUAGGGCAUCACCGGCUUUACAGUCAGACAAACCUGGGCAUUUACAUCUGUGGUCAGCCUUUUGUUUUUCUAAGUAAAAAAUUAGAUAAGAUAAAUUCCAUCUACUAUUACUAUAAUUUUUAAAAUGUUUCAUGUAACAUUGAAAAGAUUUGUAAUCUCACAGUAAAGUUUUAACUUUGUGAAAGAUGUAGGCUUUAUGUUUUCACUUUCUAUCAGAAUAGUGAAAACUUUGUUGCUAACCAGCCCUGGCCUGCAGAAUGACAUGUGAGACACUAGGAAGGACUGUCCAGACAAAGACAGCAAGAGCUGGGAUGUUUGGGAAGCAGAGGAGGGGCUGGAUCAGUGGUGAUUCCUCAGGUGCCUAUGGCAAGACCUAGUGCCCAGUUGGUGUAUGUGUGAGGAGGUGCCUGCUUCAGAGAGAACCCUGGGUGUGAUUCAGCAAGAUGGGGACGAUGAGUGGAUGGGCCGGGUGGCUGGGGGAGGCAGAGGAGUGAGCGCAGGGUCAGGCAGCAUCAGCUGUCUUGAUUUUGACUUGCUGAGUUUGCUCACAAAUGUGAGACUUUCAGAGGGGAGAUGUCCAGUGUUCACUCAGGACAGAAGACAUCCCUGACACAUGGGAGAGACACCUGGGCGCAUUCGCCUAACAGAACUACAGAGCAAGCAAGAGCAUUGAGGGGCAUGUCGAGCACGCUGAUGGACUUCCAGGACUUGGGUCUAGUGUUGCUGAGGGUGGAUCUGCAGAGCUCUGCGGCCGUCACGAUGUUCUGGAAGUUUGACUUGAACACCACGUCCCAUGUUGACAAGCUGCUGGACAAGGAGCAUGUGACGCUGCAGGAGUUAAUGGAUGAAGAUGACAUCUUGCAGGAGUGUAAGGCUCAGAACCAGAAGCUGCUGGACUUCCUGUGCAGGCAGCAGUGCAUGGAGGAGCUGGUGAGCCUCAUCACACAGGAUCCGCCCCUGGACAUGGAGGAGAAGGUCCGCUUCAAAUAUCCAAACACAGCCUGUGAGCUUCUGACUUGUGAUGUGCCGCAGAUCAGCGACCGCCUCGGUGGGGACGAGAGCCUGCUGAGCCUCCUGUACGACUUCUUGGACCAUGAGCCGCCUCUCAAUCCUCUGCUCGCCAGUUUUUUCAGCAAGACCAUUGGCAAUCUCAUUGCAAGAAAAACCGAACAGGUGAUUACGUUUUUGAAGAAGAAGGACAAGUUCAUCAGCCUGGUGUUGAAGCACAUCGGCACCUCAGCGCUUAUGGACCUGCUGCUGCGCCUGGUCAGCUGUGUGGAGCCAGCCGGGCUCCGGCAGGACGUCCUGCACUGGCUGAAUGAAGAGAAGGUCAUCCAGAGGCUUGUGGAGUUGAUCCACCCGAGCCAGGAUGAAGAUAGGCAGUCAAAUGCUUCUCAGACUCUCUGUGACAUAGUUAGGCUGGGCAGAGACCAGGGCAGUCAGCUGCAAGAGGCUCUGGAGCCAGACCCGCUCCUCACAGCGCUGGAGUCCAGGCAGGACUGUGUGGAGCAGCUUCUGAAGAACAUGUUUGAUGGAGACCGGACGGAGAGCUGCCUCGUCAGUGGGACUCAGGUGUUACUCACCUUGCUGGAAACCAGGCGGGUUGGGACAGAGGGCUUGGUGGACUCCUUUUCUCAGGGACUGGAAAGGUCAUACGCUGUCAGCAGCAGCGUACUACACGGCAUCGAGCCUCGGCUGAAGGACUUCCACCAGCUCCUGCUCAACCCGCCCAAGAAGAAAGCGAUCCUGACCACCAUUGGUGUGCUGGAGGAGCCCCUGGGGAAUGCCCGUCUGCAUGGCGCCCGCCUCAUGGCAGCACUGCUGCACACAAACACACCCAGCAUCAACCAGGAGCUCUGCCGGCUCAACACGAUGGACUUACUGCUGGACUUGUUCUUUAAGUACACCUGGAAUAACUUUUUGCACUUCCAAGUGGAACUAUGCAUAGCCGCUAUUCUCUCCCACGCUGCCCGUGAGGAGAGGACAGAAGCCAGCGGAUCCGAGAGCAGGGUGGAGCCUCCGCAUGAGAACGGGAACCGGAGCCUGGAGACUCCCCAGCCGGCCGCCAGCCUCCCUGACAACACAAUGGUGACCCACCUGUUCCAGAAGUGCUGCCUGGUGCAGAGGAUCCUGGAGGCCUGGGAAGCCAACGACCACACGCAGGCAGCGGGUGGCAUGAGACGUGGGAACAUGGGCCACCUCACACGGAUCGCCAACGCGGUGGUGCAGAACCUGGAGCGGGGCCCUGUGCAGACGCACAUCAGCGAGGUCAUCCGAGGGCUCCCUGCGGACUGCCGUGGCCGCUGGGAGAGCUUCGUGGAGGAGACGCUGACGGAGACGAACCGCAGGAACACUGUGGACCUGGUGAGCACUCACCACCUUCACUCCUCAAGUGAGGACGAGGACAUUGAGGGUGCUUUCCCUAACGAGCUGUCCCUUCAGCAGGCCUUCUCUGACUACCAGAUCCAGCAGAUGACAGCCAACUUCGUGGAUCAGUUUGGCUUCAAUGAUGAGGAGUUUGCCGACCAGGACGACAACAUCAAUGCCCCGUUUGACAGGAUCGCAGAGAUCAACUUCAACAUCGACGCUGACGAGGACAGUCCCAGCGCAGCUCUGUUUGAGGCCUGCUGCAGUGACCGCAUCCAGCCCUUUGAUGAUGAUGAGGACGAGGACAUCUGGGAGGACAGUGACACUCGCUGUGCUGCCCGGGUGAUGGCCAGACCCAGGUUUGGAGCCCCCCAUGCUUCAGAGAGUUGCUCAAAGAAUGGCCCAGAGCGUGGAGGCCAGGAUGGGAAGGCGAGCUUGGAAGCACACAGAGAUGCACCUGGGGCAGGUGCCCCACCGGCCCCCGGGAAGAAGGAAGCGCCCCCUGUGGAGGGUGACUCAGAAGGCGCCAUGUGGACGGCAGUGUUUGAUGAGCCAGCGAACUCAACGCCCACAGCCCCAGGAGUGGUGAGGGACGUGGGUUCCAGUGUGUGGGCAGCUGGCACCUCAGCUCCAGAGGAGAAAGGCUGGGCCAAGUUCACUGACUUCCAACCUUUCUGCUGCUCCGAGUCAGGGCCCAGGUGCAGCUCUCCGGUGGACACAGAAUGCAGCCAUGCUGAGGGCAGCCGGAGCCAAGGCCCUGAGAAAGCCUUCAGCCCGGCUUCUCCAUGUGCCUGGAACGUGUGUGUCACCAGGAAGGCCCCCCUGCUGGCCUCUGACAGUAGCUCCUCUGGGGGCUCCCACAGCGAGGAUGGCGACCAGAAGGCAGCGAGUGCCAUGGAUGCGGUGAGCAGGGGUCCCGGCCGGGAGGCCCCCCCGCUGCCCACAGUGGCCAGGACAGAGGAGGCUGUCGGCAGGGUCGGGUGUGCUGACAGCCGGCUGUUAAGCCCUGCCUGCCCCGCGCCAAAGGAAGUGACUGCUGCCCCAGCCGUGGCUGUGCCCCCCGAGGCUACUGUGGCCAUCACCACAGCACUGAGCAAGGCUGGCCCCGCCAUACCCACCCCAGCAGUCUCUUCUGCACUGGCCGUGGCGGUCCCCCUAGGGCCCAUCAUGGCAGUCACAGCAGCCCCAGCCAUGGUGGCCACCCUGGGGACAGUGACAAAGGACGGGAAGACAGAUGCCCCGCCAGAAGGAGCUGCCUUAAAUGGCCCAGUGUGAUGCUGCUGCCGCCCGGCCACGGCCCACCCUGGUCAGGCUGCCUCCUUAAUCGAGAAAACUACCUGGUGAUGCAAUCUUUUUUUUUUUUAAUUUAAUUUAAUUUUAAAAUAAAUGCUGCAUUGGUAAAGCUGGCAGUUGAAACCAGUUGGACGGCCCAGCUUGCGUCUCUUCUGCCUGAGUGGGCCUCUCAGGUCACUCGUGCCCUGCUGGAGGACAGAGGGGCACCUCAGCCGCCCCCAAGCCCAGAGCACAGCAAUAAGGUCGGCCUGCAGGAGCCGGGGUGGGGGUGGGGGUGGGGGGGGCAGGACCCUGAGAUGCCACCAGGACCUGAUGGGCCAGGAAGGGCGUGGACAUGGAGGCUGUUUUUACAGUUUUUUUUUUGUUGUUGUUUUGUUUUUAAAGAAUACAGAAGGAGCCAAGCUUUUUUGCACUUUGUAUCCAGCUGCAAGCUCAGGGCAGAGUCAAGGGCCUGGGUUGGAAAAACCUGACUCACAGGAAUGCAUAAUUGACCCUUGCAGCUACCCAAUAGCCCUUGGAGCUGGCACUGAACCAGGCUGCAAGAUUUGACUGCCUUAAAAACACAAGGCCCUCUAGGCCUGGCAGGGAUGUCCCUGUGCCCAGCACAGGGUGCCUGGCAGGGGGAGACCACAGGUAUGCAGGUGGGGGGACAUGGUGUGGCACUAGGGGCUCGAAGACUGGUUUCUAGCACUACCGGUCACGGCCAUGUCGUCCUAGAAGGGUCCAGAAGAUUAUUUUACGUUGAGUCCAUUUUUAAUGUUCUGAUCACCUGACAGGGCACCCCAAACCCCCAACUCCCAAUAAAAGCCGUGACGUUCGGACAAA